AUGCCUAGACACACACAUCCUUACUCUGCGUGCAUCCCUGGCCUGGUGGACGGAAGAUCGAGCGCUCUGGGUGGACUUACGGCCACAGGACGGGGGCAGAGUCGGCAGGGAGGCCCCUCCGAGGCCCAGUGGGCCCUGCGCUGGCCCCGGCCGCAGACGCCCACCUGCUGCUGUGCUGGCUGCGGCCGCCGUCUGCUGGCCACAGAGAACCCACGUGCGCCGGCCGCCAGGCCUGGGCAUCUCCUCUCCUGCAGCGCCGCCUGCUGGCCACAGAGAACCCGCGUGCGCCGGCCGCCAGGCCUGGGCAUCUCCUCUCCUGCAGCGCCGCCUGCUGGCCACAGAGAACCCGCGUGCGCCGGCCGCCUGGCCUGGGCAUCUCCUCUCCUGCAGCGCCGCCUGCUGGCCACAGAGAACCCGCGUGCGCCGGCCGCCUGGCCUGGGCAUCUCCUCUCCUGCAGCGCCGCCUGCUGGCCACAGAGAACCCGCGUGUGCCGGCCGCCAGGCCUGGGCAUCUCCUCUCCUGCAGCGCCGCCUGCUGGCCACAGAGAACCCGCGUGCGCCGGCCGCCUGGCCUGGGCAUCUCCUCUCCUGCAGCGCCGCCUGCUGGCCACAGAGAACCCACGUGCGCCGGCCGCCUGGCCUGGGCAUCUCCUCUCCUGCAGCGCCGCCUGCUGGCCACAGAGAACCCGCGUGCGCCGGCCGCCAGGCCUGGGCAUCUCCCCGGGCCCUAGUUCCCCCCCUCACCUAAGGGGAGGGACUCCCGUCUUUCCAUCCACCCCCUCCUUGCCUCUGCAGAGCUCCAGGGAAGGCUGGCACCCGCUCACUGCAUUUAGACUCCAUCAGGUUCAGACAGUGGGUCAGGGUACAAGGCUUCAGUGGCCAGGGAUGUGGCCUCUAAUUUGUAGAGAGAAAGAAGGGCAGAGGCAAAGGUUUGGGCCCAGGGACUGGGCUCCGUUUCCAGAAUCACUCUUGGAGCUGCUCUGCUGCCCCCUGCCCCAUACACGUGAUGGAGCAGAAAACGUGCUGUGUGAACCUGUGACUUCAGGGCCUGUUGACGUGGUCGUGCUUGCAUACUCUCUGGACUGGACCUCACUGUGGGAACAACAAGAUCAACAAGAGGAGCAAGAACAACAUCAAGAGUCAGGGCCCGGGGGUCCUGACGGGUACAGGACGGGUACAGACCCACACAGGAAUCCCAGAGUGUGUUCCACAGCAGGACACGCCUGCGCUGAAAGAGUGGGCAGAAAGGAGCUGACCUGGGAUUAUGAUCCAAACUCAGCUGGGCCUCCCCUCCCUGCCCCAGGAUUGUGGAGUGAGAACGUUGCAGCAGGAGAGAACAACGCAGCAAAGCACAGCAGGGGAACCGGAAAUGCUCACCUUUUGACAGGGUACUUUUAGUUCUGGGGCCUUAUCUUAAGGAUAUUCCAACAUAUACAAAAAGAUUCAUGCACAGAGAUAUUUACUUUAGUAUUAUUUACCAUAGGAAAAAAGUUGGAAACAAUACAUUUUAUGUUCUGUAAAAUGAAAGAACAGUUAAAUAAAUCAUGGCUCUAAGACGACUCCAGGGCUGUGUACGGAAGUUCAGGGACAGAAUCAGUUGAGGCUGUUCCACCUGAGCCUAAGGUUCCUCUGCUGUAUGUCGGGAAUCAGGUGGGGGCCAAGCGAGAUCACCACAGUGCAGGCCAGUGUGCAGGGCACAGGUGGGCGCCAGGGAGGGGACGCCGCACAGCCCCAUGCUCUCGCCAAAAACGUGCAGCACAAUUUGGAAGAAAACGUUUCCAUCUGUUAAUAAAGAGCAACGGCCUCUGGUCAUAAGUGA